CCCACUCCCUCACUCCAGGGCCCUGCUCGAGCCUCCUGAGUUUCGGUCUCCACCUCUCCACACUGGAAUGCCAGUGGUGUCUCCACCUCACAAGGUCGUGUGAUGAUCCCGUGGUGACACAGCAGCAUGCUGAGUACUCAGGCAGUACUGGCUCAGCUGUCUGGACAGAGGGACUGCUGUGGGACAUGUGUCCACAGCUUGAGGUGGAGAGAGCUGUGGUUGGUGUGCGCCACCCAGGGCAGGGUGGGGCUCAGGCAAUUCUGCCUGAGGUGGACACUGCAGAGGUUGGCUUUAGUUCACUGCGUAGAUGUCAAAGGCACCAAAAGAUGGCAGCUCGCGACAGAGUGAAGAGGAGGAAGUUGGAAUUGGAGUGGAGAACGCAGCCUGUCACACUUUAUACAAAAUGAUUCAGAUUCUGUAGGUCAGGGGUGAGGCCUGAGACUGCAUUUCUAACAGGCACUCAGUGAUGCUGAAGUCACUGGUCCAGAGACUGCACUUUGAGCGGCAUUCAUCCAGAACAUGAUUAAUGAUGGGGAGCCUUGUGGAGGAGAAGGUAGGGAAAAAACACGCACAGCUUAACGUAUACCCAGCUUUCUGCCUGGCUGCUUGGAGACACCUCAAAGGGGCAGGUGUUUCCAGGCGUCUGGGGUCUGUCGGGUUCUGUUGGAAUCAGAUUGUGGGUGAUGAUGGAGACUGAUCGUAAGAGCCCGGUGAGAGCUUUGGGAGACGUAUGGAGUGAUUUGAUUUUGUUGCUUGAUAUCUCAUCCCUCACAGUCUGGCUUCACAGUUAUAUCCUCCUUAGAAGGCAUCGCUUUCUGCCGGAGGCUGAGCCAUGGUCACACCCUGGAAGGUCCUCUGUCUUAGCACUCCCCACAUGGAAAGCUGUGAUUUCUGCAUCCCUCUCUCUCUGAUUGAUUUGUGAGUUCCCGGAGAGCUAGGAACUGAGACAGCCUCUUAACCUUGUACCCCAGCACCUGCCUCACAGCUGGUGUUAGUGAGAGGGGUGGAUACAGGUUUUGAAGGAAGAAUGAGUAAAGCCUGUGAUCAAAAGGGAGUAGGAGAGCCCAGCACCGAGCUGGGGCACUGGAGCCUGUCGCUGUGGACAGGAGGCCCAGCUAUGGCAUUAGCCAGGCCUUUGGUGAAAUUGCCAGGAACAUGGUCUAAAGGGUACUCGCAUAUUGGGCGUCAGCUCUGAGGAGCGAGGGCUGGGCUGUGAGUUCUCUGAAGGUGUGGAGGGCUCCAUGGGGGAAUGGCAGUUUCAGCCAAGAAGCUAUCAUGUUGAUCUGGGAGCCAAGAGCAAACCUACUUUUCUUCUGCUGCCUUCAGGAAAGGACAGGUGCCCAGAUUUAUGCAGACUGGGGAUCAAGACUUUUCUCCCUGUGCAUCAGGGCAUGGAUAGCAGCUCUUCCUGAGGCUGAGUAGAAGCAGCAGAUAGGGCUCCAACACCGGGCAGUGUCUAGAGCAGCCCACAGCCUUAGCACCUGCGAGUGCUGACGAGGACCCUGUGGGUUAAUGUCAGUUUCAUUUUCCUGAGGAGGAAAUGGAAUCUCAGUGAGGUUCAGUAACUUGUCCAAAGCCACAGAUCUGGGAAGUGGAGGAGGCAGCCCAGCACUGGAGCUGGUUUCUGGGGGAGGAGUGGGUCCAGGUAUGGAUUAAAAGGCCAGAGCAUUGCAGAGGUGGUAGGGCAGGGCAGACAGUGGAUAGUGGGAGGGAACCCAGGAAGAGGAAGCAGGGUUGGGGAUGCAGAAAUGGGACAGGAGGCAGCAGAGAGUCAGAGGACGGAGAUUUAAGCAGUUUAACACCCUAGCACCAAUAAAGCAUUAGGUGACAGCAUUUAAAACAAAAAAAAUUAGAUCAGUUUGACUUUCUUCUGACUCAUGAUUGCUCAUCAUAGAAAAUAACAGAAAAGUUGAAAGAAUAGAAAAACUAACACAUGUGGGGUUUUUUUGUCUUUCAGAUUCCUUUGUUUUAAUUAGUUGCGGUUAUCCCGUAGAUACAACUUUAUAACAAGCCUCUUAAUAUUCUAAUCACACAGACAUCCUGUGGCUGUUUUGUGGCUUACUUAACUGGCCGUCCGAAAUUGGCAAGUAGCUUUUUUGUUUGUAAUUUUCAGUGUUAUAAAUGUUGCUGGGAGGAAAAUCUCUGCAACUAAAACUUUUUUUCAUGUCUGAAUAUAUCCUGACAGCAGGUUCCUAGAAAUGGAAUUACUUAGUCAGACUGCCUUCCAGCCCCAUUGGAAUGGUAUGCUGUGUUAGCGCUGACACAAGCCUUCUAAAAGUGCAGGUGUAAUCCCUGCGCGCAUUAGUUGUUCAUUCAUUCAUUUGUGCAUUUCACACACAUUUCUUAAGCGCCUAUGGGCAGAGGCUCCAUUUUCUAUGGCCUGAUCAGCAGGGGAGCAGCUGCCAGCAUCUUGGACCUGACCGAAAGGCGGGGGAGUUUCUGACUGUACACAAUGUCCCAGCCCUCCCUGUCUUUGUCACAGGCCCAGGAGCGCUGGACAGCCUAUGGGUCCAGAAGUAAACUUGGGUGCCUCUGUGGCUACAGGGUCCAGGCAGUGCCCACCCAUCUGCCUUCCCCUCUUGUGACACUUAGUGACAUGCUACACACUGAGUAUGGGGUUCCCAAUUUUAUCAAUUUAUUCAUGCAUUCCAUAGAUACUUAGUGCCUCAUGUGCACUGGACACUGUUCUAGAUGCCAUGGAGAUGGCAGUUCACUACUAAAAUCCCUGCCUUUAAGGAACUUACAUUUAAGGAGAAAUCUAAAGUAGGGUGAGAGGGAGAAGGAGUGAUCAGGGAAGGCCUCACUGAUGAGGUAAAAUUUAAGCAGGCACAUGAAGAAACUGAGUGAGAGAGCCAGGUGCAUAUCUAAGGGAAGGGUGUUCAAGGAGAGGGAACAGCACGUGCAAACACCCAAGGUUGGAACAAGCUUGGCACCACCUGGGAACAGCCAGAGAAGCAUGAGACCCUGGUGGAGCAGAAUGAGAUCUAGGACUCAGGGUUCAUUUCCCCAUCCCCUUUGGAGAUUUUAGAACCAGAGGGCCACCCCUCCUCUGUGAAGCAGUUCAAACUAACCUCAUGUAUUUCUCUUGCUUAUCUAUAGUUGGCCAUCACUGAGACCUGUGUUCGGUGGGCUCUGGCUUUGGAAGUCCCUGCCAUGCCCUGCCCUGCCCUUGGGUUUCCUUAUCUGUGCACUGAGGGACUUGAACCAGGAGACUGGCAAGGGUACAUUGGGCUUUCCUCUGUCUUGUCCAGUUAGGUCUGUGAGUUAGAUCUUGGGUAAUUUUUAGGUUAAUAUUAGGAGUGUGUAAAUGCCGUUGUUGAUAUUUAAUUCUUAAUAUGUUUAGCCUAUUAGAUUUCCUUUGUUAUGAAAGAGUCUCCCAGCCAGCUGUGGGCAGCAGUCAUAAGAAGUGAGUGGAGGGAUAAACCUAGUGGUUUAUCCAUCAACCAUCCAACCAUGCAUCCAUGCAUCCAUCCAUCCAUCCAUCCAUCCAUCCAUUCAUCCCACAGUGAAUUAUUGAGCACCUGUUGGGUACCAGCCACUGGGCAGGCUGCCUGUGCGGCAGUGGUGAGAUUUUAAAGACUCAGACCCAGCCUUUUUGUGUAGGGAUGUUAGCUCUGCCAGAAGAUCGUGCUGGUGAAGGACUCCACUCAGCAAGACCAGAGCAGCUAACACAUCAUACCAUAUACAAAAAUUCACUCAAAAUGGAUCAAUGACCUUAAUAAAAGACCCUAAAGCCAUAAAACUCCUAGAAGAAAACAUAGGGGUAAACCUUCACAACCUUGAAUUUGGCAAUGAAUUCUUGGAUAUGACACUAAAAAUGCAAGUAACAAAAGAAAAAUAAAUUGGGACUUCAUGAAAAUUAAAGCUUUUUUGCAUCCAAAGACAUCAUCAAGAAAGUGAAAAGGCAACCUAUGGAAUGAGAGAAUAGGCCAGGCGCAGUGGCUCCCACUUGUGAUCCCAGCACCUUGGGAGACUGAGGCAGGCAGAUCAUUGAGUCUAGGAGUUCAAGAUGAGCCUGGGCAACAUGGUGAAACCCCGUCUCUACAAAAAAUACAAAAAUUAGCCAGGUGUGGUGUGUGCCUGUAGUCCCAGCUACUAAGGAGACUGAGGCUGGAGGAUCACUUGGGAGACACAGGUUACACUGAGCCAAGAUGGUGCUACUGCCCUCCAGCCUGGGUGACAGAGCGAGACCCUGAAAGUCAACAGCUCACACUAACACAAAACAAAUUUUAAAAAUGGGCAGAAGACUUGAAUAGACAUUUCUCUAAAGAUGCACAAAUUGCCAGUAAACACAUGAAAAGAUGCUCAGCAUCAUUAGUCAUUACGGAAAAUGUAAAGUAAAGCCACAAUGAGACACCACUGCACACCUACUAGAAUGGUUAUGAUCAAAAACAGGAAACUAACAAGUAUUAGCAAGGAUGUGGAGGAAUAGUAACCCUCUUAUAUUGUGGUGGGAAUGUAAAAUGGUGCAGCCUCUGUAGAAAACAAUCUGAUUAUUCCCCAAAAAGCUGUACAUAAUAGGGCCAGGCACAGAGGCUCAGGCCUGUAAUCCCAGCACUUUGGGAGGGUGUAUCGCUUGAGCUCAGGAGUUUGAGACCAGCCUGGGCAACAGGGCGAAACCCAGUCUACCAAAAGUACAAAAGCUUAGCUGGGCGUGGUGGCACACACUUGUAGUCCCAGCUACUAGGGAAGCUGAGAUGGGAAGAUCCAUUGAGCCUGGGAGGCGGAGGAGGCUGCAGUAAGCUGAGAUGGUGCCUUUGCACUCCAGCCUGGGCAACAGAGGAAGACUGUGUCUCAAAAAAAUUUUAAAAAGCUAUAGAUAGAACUACCAUGUGACCCAGCAAUCCUACUCCUACGUAUAUACCUGAAAGAAUUGAAAGUGGACUCGGACAGAUACUUGUAUGCUGAAAUGAUAAAAUUUAAGCAUUGCAACACCAUUCACAAUAGCCAGAAGGCAGAAACAACCCAAAUGUCCAAUGACAGAUGAAUUGAUAAACAAAAUGGAAUAUCAUUCAGUCAUAAAAAGAAAUAAAGUUCUGAUACAUGCUAAAAUAUGGAGGAACCUUAAAAACAUGCUAAGUGAAAUAAGCCAGACUCAAAUAGACAAAUACUAUGUGGUUCCACUGAUGUAUCUAGACUAGGCAAAUUCGUAGAGGCAGAAAGUAGAUUAGAGGUGGCCAGGAGUUGGAGGAGGGGUGAAUGGGGAGUUAUUGCCUAAUGGGUACAGAGUUUCUGUUUGGGAUGAUGAAAAAUUUCUGGAAAUAGUGGUAAUGUUUGCACAACAUUGUGAAUAUAAUUAAAGCCACUGAAUUGUACACUUAAAAAUGGCUAAAAUGGCAAGCGUUAGGUCCUAUAUAUUUUACAAUUAAAAAAAAAAAAAACGCUUGUUUACCGGAGAUUUAAAAGAACAGAAAAAAAGAAAAGAAAAAGAAAAGACCAGAAGAGGUAGUGGGAGGAGCACGUCUUUGGCAGGAGCCACCGGUUUGGAUUCUGCCCUGCCGCUGGGUCACCUCAGAAACACAUGUGGUAACCUCAUGGGCGAAGCCUGGUCCCCUCUUUUGAUGUGAGAGUCCAGUAAGAUGGUUAUUCAGCGAUAGUUAUGACCUCCCGGUUACGUGCGUUGGGUGGAAGAAUUAAUAAUAUACGCACCUCGGAGUUACCCAAAGAGAAAACUCGAUCAGAAGUCAUUUGCAGCAUCCACUUUUUAGAUGGCGUGGUACAGACCUUUAAAGUUACUAAACAAGACACUGGCCAGGUUCUUCUGGAUAUGGUGCACAACCACCUGGGUGUGACUGAAAAGGAAUAUUUUGGUUUACAGCAUGAUGACGACUCCGUGGACUCUCCUAGAUGGCUGGAAGCAAGCAAAGCCAUCAGGAAGCAGUUAAAAGGAGGUUUCCCCUGUACCCUGCAUUUUCGAGUAAGAUUUUUUAUACCUGAUCCCAACACACUGCAGCAAGAACAAACCAGGCACUUGUAUUUCUUACAACUGAAGAUGGAUAUUUGCGAAGGAAGGUUAACCUGCCCUCUUAACUCAGCAGUGGUUCUAGCGUCCUAUGCCGUACAAUCUCAUUUUGGAGACUAUAAUUCUUCCAUACAUCAUCCAGGCUAUCUUUCCGAUAGUCACUUUAUACCCGAUCAAAAUGAGGACUUUUUAACAAAAGUCGAAUCUCUGCAUGAGCAGCACAGUGGGCUAAAACAAUCAGAAGCAGAAUCCUGCUAUAUCAACAUAGCGCGGACCCUCGACUUCUAUGGAGUAGAACUGCACAGUGGUAGGGAUCUGCACAAUUUAGACCUAAUGAUUGGAAUUGCUUCCGCGGGUGUUGCUGUGUACCGAAAAUACAUUUGCACAAGUUUCUAUCCUUGGGUGAACAUUCUCAAAAUUUCUUUCAAAAGGAAAAAGUUCUUCAUACAUCAGCGACAGAAACAGGCUGAAUCCAGGGAACAUAUUGUGGCCUUCAACAUGCUGAAUUACCGAUCUUGCAAAAACUUGUGGAAAUCCUGUGUUGAGCACCAUACGUUCUUUCAGGCAAAGAAGCUACUACCUCAGGAAAAGAAUGUUCUGUCUCAGUACUGGACUAUGGGCUCUCGGAACACCAAAAAGUCGGUAAAUAACCAAUAUUGCAAAAAGGUGAUUGGCGGGAUGGUGUGGAACCCAGCCAUGCGGAGAUCCUUAUCAGUGGAGCACUUAGAAACCAAGAGUCUGCCUUCUCGUUCCCCUCCCAUUACUCCCAACUGGCGAAGUCCUCGGCUCCGGCACGAAAUCCGAAAGCCACGCCACUCUUCUGCAGAUAACCUUGCAAAUGAAAUGACCUACAUCACGGAAACGGAAGAUGUAUUUUACACGUACAAGGGCUCUCUGGCCCCUCAAGACAGCGAUUCUGAAGUUUCUCAGAACCGAAGCCCGCACCAAGAGAGUUUAUCCGAGAACAAUCCGGCACAAAGCUACCUGACCCAGAAGUCAUCCAGUUCUGUGUCUCCAUCUUCAAAUGCUCCAGGCUCCUGCUCACCUGACGGCGUUGAUCAGCAGCUCUUAGAUGACUUCCACAGGGUGACCAAAGGGGGCUCCACCGAGGACGCCAGCCAGUACUACUGUGACAAGAAUGAUAAUGGUGACAGCUACUUAGUCUUGAUCCGUAUCACACCAGAUGAAGAUGGAAAAUUUGGAUUUAAUCUUAAGGGAGGAGUGGAUCAAAAGAUGCCUCUUGUGGUAUCAAGGAUAAACCCAGAGUCACCUGCGGACACCUGCAUUCCUAAGCUGAACGAAGGGGAUCAAAUCGUGUUAAUCAAUGGCCGGGACAUCUCAGAACACACGCAUGACCAAGUGGUGAUGUUCAUCAAAGCCAGCCGGGAGUCCCACUCACGGGAGCUGGCCCUGGUGAUCAGGAGGAGAGCUGUCCGCUCAUUUGCUGACUUCAAGUCUGAAGAUGAACUGAACCAGCUUUUCCCCGAAGCCAUUUUCCCCAUGUGUCCGGAGGGUGGGGACACUUUGGAGGGAUCCAUGGCACAGCUAAAGAAGGGCCUCGAAAGCGGGACGGUGCUGAUCCAGUUUGAGCAACUCUACAGAAAAAAGCCAGGUUUGGCCAUCACGUUUGCAAAGCUGCCUCAAAAUUUGGACAAAAACCGAUAUAAAGAUGUGCUGCCUUAUGACACCACCCGGGUAUUAUUGCAGGGAAAUGAAGAUUAUAUUAAUGCAAGUUACGUGAACAUGGAAAUUCCUGCUGCUAACCUUGUGAACAAGUACAUCGCCACUCAGGGGCCCCUGCCGCAUACCUGUGCACAGUUUUGGCAGGUUGUCUGGGAUCAGAAGUUGUCACUCAUUGUCAUGUUGACGACUCUCACAGAACGAGGGCGGACCAAAUGUCACCAGUACUGGCCAGAUCCCCCCGACGUCAUGAACCACGGCGGCUUUCACAUCCAGUGUCAGUCAGAGGACUGCACCAUCGCCUAUGUGUCCCGAGAAAUGCUGGUCACAAACACCCAGACCGGGGAAGAACACACAGUGACACAUCUCCAGUACGUCGCAUGGCCUGACCACGGUGUGCCCGAUGACUCCUCCGACUUUCUGGAAUUUGUAAACUAUGUGAGGUCUCUGAGAGUGGACAGCGAGCCCGUCCUAGUUCACUGCAGUGCUGGAAUAGGUCGAACCGGUGUGUUGGUCACUAUGGAAACAGCCAUGUGCCUAACUGAGAGGAACCUGCCCAUUUACCCACUGGAUAUUGUCCGAAAAAUGCGAGACCAGCGCGCCAUGAUGGUGCAGACAUCAAGCCAGUACAAGUUUGUGUGUGAAGCGAUUCUUCGUGUGUAUGAAGAAGGUUUAGUCCAAAUGCUGGAUCCUAGUUAAGACAACUGUGAAAAAGUUCAUUCCUCUUUCCCAAGGGCAUCCUCCUUGAAAGAGGAGGACAGACCUCUCUGGAAGCAGCAAGAGGAACCAGUAGCUGUGGGAAAGGAAUGGGCACCUCUGAACCCAGGCACUUUAAACUUCUAUAGAAAAGAUAUCGUGUACAUAGGAACUGGUGUAGAUAAGCAUGCAAUUAUGGCAUCAUUUAGGCCUGUAUUUCUAUGGAAAGAUACAAAAAGGAUCUCAGUUUGGGGCCUGUCCUAAUGCCUUCUUCCCUAACAUCACCACACACACCCCUGUCGGCAUCCUGGAGCAAUUGAGACCGGACACCCACAGAGCUGUUGUCCUCCCAGCAACAAGAUGGUGUGGUUAUCUUGGGUCAUUUGGAUGUUUUGUUUGUUUCUGUGUGUCAGACUGUAAGGGCUGAGCUUUCUGUGCUUCUAGGUGGAGCUGGAACAAUUCAGAUUCACCCGCCCUGAUGCUAAGGAAACCCUGACGUAUGUACUAGAUGGCAGGGCACUGGGGGUCAGGCUGAAGGCUGAGCAACACCUCUCUGCCCUCCCUCCCUUUGUCCCAUCUCCCAGCGACUUCCAAUAUUCAUGUUUCUGAGAAUUGUGUCCCUCUUCAGGUUCCCUCUUGGUGCCUAACCUGGAUUAGUAAUGUGCAUUCAGGUGAAUUUUCAGCUGAGGCUCUGAGAACUGGUACUCUCAGUGUGUUCUGGUCAUCUUGUGGCUUAGUUGUAGAAGCAGGUGUGUCUCUUGCCUCUGCUUGCCUCCUACUGCACACUCAGCACCCAGGACUGGAAUCACCGACUACUGAAUCUCCUACAUGUAUUGCUGCUACUUCAAGCUCCUCCACUUGAAACCUUAUGAUUUUCCCAAGGGGAGAUGGGACAGUGUCAUCUAAAUAUUCCGAAUGUUUGGCCUUCUGAGAAAAGAGCUUCUAGUAAUUGAACCAUGGGAAACCCAGCUUCUGGAGGGUUGGCCGUGGGGCUGUGUACAUGUGUGUGCCCAGGGGUGAGUGUUUCUCAGGAUUCCUAACGAUUCAAAUUACCGUUGAGUAUAUAUAAAGAAUGAGUCUCUGUAUGGAAGAACAAAUGUGUGCAUUCACCCCCAGUCACAAUGGUCUCCAUUGCAUUUCAAAGGAGAGGAUCAGACUAUCUGAAUAUAAACACAAUCUGAUGUUAAUUUAUUCUAAGAACACCAUCAUUUUGAUUGUCCUAAAGAAUUCUGCCUUUGUGAAUACCGUGUUAAAUUUUUUUAAAUUUGUGACAGGAUUGUAGCAAAUUAUUAUUUAAGGAAAAUAAAUUGUGUAAACAUUUAAUGUGGUAUUUUUGAACAGCGGUUUUUAUGUACUCAGAAGAGGAAGUAAAGCCAGGUUCUUAAUGGUAUUUAUAGAAAAGAUGUUUUCAUAUUAUAAUGCACAUAAAUGAAGCCAUUUUGAUAUUCAGCAAAUUCGGUGCCAAUUGAAUAGUUUGCUGGUAGCAAGACGGAUGAAGACCUAUAUGGGAGAUUCUUUAUCUCUAGAGCUAGCAUAUUUACUUGCAUACUUUGUUUCUUUUCCACAUGGAUAUUUUACUGCUAAAUGGCAGAGGUGGGAGGGAGAUGUCACACAGUACCAUAACCCCAUAUUGAAAACAAGAAACCACCAGAAAGUUUGCAGCUAAGGGGCAGGGGAUUCAGUUCCUACGCCCACUCAGCACUAACUACUUGCGGGCCUGGUUGCUUAGAAGCUCUACCUCUCUUUCAUUAUCUGUAAAAUAGAAACAAUACUUAGGACUUUAGUUGGAACAUGAGGAUUGAAUAAGAUCACGCUAUUCAUGUGACUUUUUAUCGGCUAGAACAGCAACAGACACUGCUGUGGGUGAGUUACUUAGAAAAGUUUAGUUAUCAGUGAUUAGCCCAAAAACACAUCAGUCAAAAAUAGAAUCCACUGGAUUUUUGUCUCUCUUUUUAGAGACAGGGUCUCACUGUCGCCCAGGCUGGAGUACAGUGGCAUGAUCAUUGUUCACUGCAGCCUCAAAUUCCUGGGCUCAAGCAAUCCUCGCACCUCAGCCUCCUGAGUAGCCGGGACUAUAGGCACAUGCCACCUCACCUGGCUUGUGUGUGUGUGUGUGUGUGUGUGUGUGUGUGUGUGUGUGUGUGUGUGUGUGUGUGUGUGUGUAGAGACAGGAUCUUGAUGUGUUGCCUAGGCUGGUCUCAAACUCCUGGCCUCAAGUGAUCUUCCCACCUCAGCCUCCAAAACUGUUGGGAUUAUAGGCGUGAGCCACUGUGCCCAGCCUAACUGGGUUUUUAUGAGAGGAAAAUAGAAAAUGCUCUUCUAGAAGAGAGAGAACAAGAGCACAAAAUAAUCUGGACUCACAAAAAUUCAGCAAGCUCCAAGAAAGGGGGAUGGAGGGAACGCUGGCAAAAAUUUAAAUGCCAUUAGGAUAUUUAGCAAGUUAUUACUGUUUGGUAAAAAUGCAUCAUCACCCUGUGUGCAAAAUGCUUGCAAAGUAGUCUAAAUGUCUUUGGAGAUGGGUGUUUUACUGCUUUUUUCCAAAAACAAAUUGUUUAUUAUGGUUGCAGAAAUGCAGCCAUUACGGUCACAUAAAUUUCUAAAAAGCCUACCAAAGGUUGCAAGCAGUCUUCUGCCACUGGGCAGGCCAGCAGUUCAGACCCAGCGAGGUUGCCAGGAACAAAUCCAGGAAAUACUGGGAAGAACAAGACAAGAGAAUUACCUAAAAGAGCAAACAAUUCAAGUAAAUCCUGUAGCUAUUACCACUUAAAAUCCGUAGCUCAAGAUUCCUGUUUCACCACCUUAUACACUUAAGCAAUUAUACUUAAGCCUUUUUUUAGUCCUAAGUGAAGAACUACAUCAGAAUCAGGAUAAGUAUUUUGCCUGGGAAAUUUGGCUGCAUAUGAAUGGAGAAGACAUUUACAUCCUAUGUUCUGGCACUUUCUGAAAGAUCUAAUUAAACAUGUUGAUGUGCCAAUUUAAUCAAGAUGAGAGAUCCCUGCUGGUGUCACCCUCUAGAACCUGCACUUGGUGUUUUGACUUUCCAGAAGAAAAAAAUGCAACUUUGGUUAGGGGGCAGUGGUUGGAUCACACAGUUGUCUUUCGUUUCCUACCACAGUAAUUCAUAUUUAAAUAUGCUUUUAGAUUAGUGUGGAUACUAUUGCUGCUGUGUUGCUACCUGACCUUUUUCUGGGGGGGGUACCUCAGAAAUGAGCAUUUGAGGGCAAGCGAAAAAGCCCUCUUCAUCCUCCAGAGGCAACAAAGAGGCAGCAGAAAUGGGGAAAGAUUGUGAGAGGCAGGGCUUGGGUCUAGACCUGGACUUAGGCAAGAUAUGUUGCCCUCAACCCUGAGUUUUCUUAUAUGUAAAAAGGGAAGGUUGGGCUGGACUAGAUGAGGUCAAGAUUUGCCAUUCUGGGAGGCUGAUAUUCCAGAGAAUCAAAAUUAAUCCUAAACCAAAGCUUUAUGGCUGCUACAGAGACAUGUCACAUUUCUGAGACUUGUCACCAAGAGUUUGUCCCUCAGACUUUGGCGCUGUUGAAUGCAAAGACAAGGAUGGCCACCUUCUGGUUCUUGCCUGUUGUCCUCAGCUGAGAGCAGUCUCGGUAAAGGUGGCAAAGAUUCUGUGACCUCAGACCGGGGACCAAAUGCUUGGGAGUCUGAUGGCCGGGCUGGGCCACCAUUCUCAUAGCUCUCAUUCUGUUUGGAGCAACCAAAGGAUUUGUGUGAAGUUAUUUGGAAAAGGACCUUAACUGAGCAGUAAUCUUUUUUCUGUAUAUUUGGAAUGUUUUUCAUUCUGACCUGUUCUGUCAGUGAUUCUACUGAAAAACAAUUUAAUCAAUAUAAAAAUGUUCAAGCUAUGCAA